CCUUUCUGCAGAGUCCCGGCAGUGCGGGACUCCGGUAGCCGCCCCUCCGGUAGCCGCCCCUCCUGCCCCCGCGCCGCCGCCCUAUAUGUUGCCCGCCGCGGCCUCUGGGGCAUGGAGCACGCUGCCCAGCCCUGGCGAUGGCAACGGCGACGGGGGUGGCGGAGGAGCGCCUGCUGGCCGCGCUCGCCUACCUGCAGUGCGCCGUGGGCUGCGCGGUCUUCGCGCGCAAUCGUCAGACGAACUCAGUGUACGGCCGCCACGCGCUGCCCAGCCACAGGCUCCGAGUGCCGGCGCGGGCCGCCUGGGUGGUGCAGGAGCUGCCCUCGCUGGCCCUGCCGCUCUACCAGUACGCCAGCGAGUCCGCCCCGCGUCUCCGCAGCGCGCCCAACUGCAUCCUCCUGGCCAUGUUCCUCGUCCACUACGGGCAUCGGAAAUGUUGGUAUGCAAGCACUUGCAGUGUGCCUACAUCCCAAAUGCCAGCCCAUGGUACCCAUUGUCUGCCCGGAUCUGAAUCAUGAUUCCAAGACGCAGAGAGAAAUUGCUGGGAUUCGUUGUUCUUAUUCAUUGCUUGGCAACACUGCAGCUUCCAGGAGAAUACCCACCUCACUGAUGACACAACAUCUGAAUGCACACUUACUGGCCAACACGUGCUUUGCUGUAAAUCAGUAUGAAGUCUUCCUAGGGGUCCUGGCCUGAAUGAGAUGAGAACCUUGGAGGCUGCUUUUGACUCAUGUGAAUGUCUUCCCCAGGAGUUAAGUGGGAGUGCUGGGGAGAGAGUGGCUUGAGGAUGCACAGCCAGCAUGACACUACUAUUAUGUGAUUACUGUCGACGUUCAUAACCAUAACUAAUGACUAAUUAUGACUUUACCCUGGCGCACAUGGUCAGAAUGGAAACAAAUAACAAGCUUUACAGUUUUUCCUGCUCUAUUAAGGUGCUUAAUUUACCCAUUUCUGAUGCGAGGAGGAAAGCCUAUGCCACUGUUGGCGUGUACAAUGGCGAUUAUGUUCUGUACCUGUAACGGCUAUUUGCAAAGCAGAUACUUGAGCCAUUGUGCAGUGUAUGCUGAUGACUGGGUAACAGAUCCCCGUUUUCUAAUAGGUUUUGGCUUGUGGUUAACGGGCAUGUUGAUAAACAUCCAUUCAGAUCAUAUCCUAAGGAAUCUCAGAAAACCAGGAGAUACUGGAUACAAAAUACCAAGGGGAGGCUUAUUUGAAUACGUAACUGCAGCCAACUAUUUUGGAGAAAUCAUGGAGUGGUGUGGCUAUGCCCUGGCCAGCUGGUCUGUCCAAGGCGCGGCUUUUGCUUUCUUCACGUUUUGUUUUUUAUCUGGUAGAGCAAAAGAGCAUCAUGAGUGGUACCUCCGGAAAUUUGAAGAGUAUCCAAAGUUCAGAAAAAUUAUAAUUCCAUUUUUGUUUUAAGUGCGUUUUUCAUGAAAUUAUCUUCAACUUGAAGCUUUCCAAUGGCGCUUCUCUAUGGACUUUGUAAAUAAGUUAUAUCUUUGUAAUUUUCCUGCUACUUUAUCAUUUUCAAGAUGUCCUCUAGGAAUUUUUUUUCUAGUAAUUUUGCAAUCUACCUAAUAAGUACCUAAAUACGCUGAAAUGGAGGUUGAAUAUCCUACUGUGUAACAGGUCAGAAUUUCAAGCUCUGGGUAAUAACUGCUGAUAUUUUUUCUAAUUUCAAAUUUACCUCUUUUGGCUAUGUCUUGCCAAGUGUGUAUGAGACUAGACUUUACAACUGUCUUUGAUGGCAUUUUCAGAACAAUAAAUGUCACAAUCCCUUCUAUAGCCCCCUACAGUGAUCUCUUCAAGGUCAACUGCAGUGUUGCUUCCCUCCCCCUAUAGGGCUGGAAUCUGUCUAGGAGCCCUCUCUCGGAGGCCACAGAGGCUGGGGGUAGCCAUUGUGCAGUCAUGGCCCGGGGGAAACUUGCCAACCUUCGUGUCAGGUGCUGUGUGUAAGUGGAGAACUUGGGGAUAGAGGAGGAAGCUCCUCGUGGCCCUUCCAAGGUGAGGCAAAGGCAUCUGGACUUGUUCCAGCCCAGCCCACCGGGUGACAUCACCGGGCAGGGAGGGGUGCUGGUGGUGGUUCAUACGGAGUAAGCUGCUCUGCCUGUGUGAGUGGCUCCUGGGCCCUAAACAGGCACCUUUAGGCCAUGGGUCACUCACCGUGAGCCAUCAAUGUGCUCUGGUCUGACAUGGUUUCUCUCUGUCUUCUAGUCUAGACCUAGUUUUUUUGUUCUGUUCCCCACGUAUGGAUAUAGUAGAGAUUGUUGUCUGUGAAAUUUCUCUUUUGUAGAUUUUGAGUUUUCCCUUGUAGUGUAAAGAAUGAUCACUUUCUGUAACAAUAACAAGACCACUUUUUAAGAUUUAUCCUGUUUGUUCUUUGUUGAUUGAAACAUAAUAAUUGUUAAAAUUCUCUACAGCCUUCUUUUUCUUCCAUAGCUAAUCUUCCUUCUAAUAGUUUUUGCUUUCUGUUUUGCUGUUGUUGCUUUGCAAAGCUUUCCCCUCAUAGCCUGUACCUGUUAUCAAUAUAAAAUAAUCUUCCUGUUGAAUGCUUCAUGACUUGAAUUCUACUUUGAUAAAAACAUUGCCAUACUGCUUUUUAUCUUGAUGAAUUCAUCUGGCAUUGCUUUGCCUUAUCAUCUCAUCUGGAGUUUUUAAAUGCCAUUUGUUUCAGUUGUCUUUAACAACAUAAUAAAUAGACUUUGCCAUUUAACAAGGUAGCUCAAAUUCUUUUACUAAUUGUUACAUCGAAACAUUCUUUCAUCAUAUUUCCUGUUUUUAUUUGGUUUUUUCAACUUCUUCUGUUUACUAUCUACAGUGAUUUGGAAAGGAGAUUUCCUUUAAAACAAACAAGCUUAUUGGGAAUGGCUUUUAUGAUUUUUAAAGUAGCCUUGAGAGCUUCCAGUUAAAUCUGAUGAGCUGAACAUACACCUUUCCUUCUCCCCUCUCUAUUCUGACCCCAGUUGAAAUCACCUCAAAGGAAUUUAGGUGGGGGAGUGGCCCCAUAAAGAGAGUGAGAGAGAGUCACCACUGCAGAUGGACCACAGCACGGGUGGAGAUGGGCCUGAUGUGGCAGAGCAGAGAGGCCAUGACAGUGCACACCCUGCGGAGACCCUGGGUCCUCACAUCUGGGCUGACAGAAGGCAGAGGGAAAUGAGCAUCUCAAAGUGAGACCAACUAAACAUGGCGCCUGCAGCAGAAAGCAGUGUCCUCUGCACCCCCACUCUCCAGGGAGAGCACAGAGAGCCCAGAAAUGAGCCAUGUGCCCAUUGCCGGGGAAGAGAAGGUAGGCUGAGGAGGUGGCCUUUCCUAACACAAAAAUUAACUAAGUGGGGAAAACCAGAGAACUAGGUGUUGGCAUCCCAGGAAAAAAAUAAAGUCUCCACAUUUUGGCCUAUAGGGAUCCUGCCCCAUAAUGGCUGGUUACCUCCUGCCUCAAGCUGCAGGGAAGCCAGGGGGUGGCAUGGCCAUGGCUUCUCCCUCAGAGAGGCCUCUGUGCACGACUUCAGUCACCCAACACUGACAGAACUUGGAACCCAAAAGCCCAUUUCUCUCCUUCCGUCCAGACCCUGUCUGCUGUUAUCUGUAGGAAGACCACAGCCAACUGCUAUCAUGACCAAAGCUAAAAUCCAAUGAGGCAGAGAACAAUAGUUGUACCCAUCUCCUCCUUAGUCUCCAAGGCCAGCGGUGCAUGCAUUUGUGCAUUCAACAACAUUUGCCAAGCACUUACUGUAUAUCAAGCACAGCAGUGGGUGCUGAGGACGGAUGGGUAGAAAAAACAGUCCUGGCCCAGGUGGAGUGACAGGUAAGAAACAAGUAAGUAGCUAAAAUAAUGUUAGGUAGAAAAAAAUAACAAGAAUAAAAGCAAGGAAAAGGGAAGGGACCCUCACUUGUGUCUGAUACAGCCAUAAUCUUCUCUAUCGGCCAUUGCUGUAACCAAAGCUUAACCACCUUUCUUAAGAUAUUGAUCAACCAGAUCAUUGCAAAUACUGCUAAUUGAUUCCUUUUUAUGGCUGAGUAGUAUUCCAUUGUAUAUAUAUAUAUACCACUUGUUGACUGAUGGGCAUUUGGGUUGGUUCCACGAUUUUGCAGUUGUGAAUUGUGCUGCUAUAAACAUGUGCGUGCAAGUAUCUUUUUUUGAAUAAUGACUUCUUUUCCUCUGGGUAGAUACCCAGUAAUGGGAUUGCUGGAUCAAAUGGUAGUUCUACUUUUAGUUCUAAGGAAUUUCCACACUGUUUUCCAUGGUGGCUCUAAUAGUUUACAUUCCCACCAGCAGUGUGGAAGUGUUCCAUGAUUGCCGCAUGCAUGCCAACAUCUACUGUUUUUUGAUUUUUUUGGUUAUGGCCGUUCUUGCAGGAGUAAGGGGGUAUCGCACUGUAGUUUUUAUUUGCAUUUCCCUGAUCAUUAGUGAUGUUGAGCAUUUUUUCAUACUUUGUUGGCCAUUUGUAUAUCUUCUUUUGAGAAUUGUCUAUUCAUGUCCUUAACCCACUUUUUGAUGGGAUUGUUUGUUUUUUUCUUACUGAUUUGUUUGAGUUUGUUGUAGAUUCUGGAUAUUAGUCCUUUGUCUGAUGUAUAGAUUGUGAAGAUUUUCUCCCACUCUGUGCGUUGUCUGUUUACUCUGCUGACUGUUGCUUUUACCAUGCAAAAGCUCUUUAGUUUAAUUAAGUCCCAUCUAUUUAUCUUUGUUUUUAUUGUUGGAAACUAUUAUUCUAAGUUAAGUAACUCAGGAAUGGAAAACCAAACAACCUAUGUUCUCAUUGAUAUGUGGGAGCUAAGCUAUGAGGACACAAAGGCAUAAGAAUGGUACAAUGGACUUUGGGGACUUGGGGGGAAGGGUAAGGGGGGGUGAGGAAUAAAAGACAACAUAUAUGGUAUAGUAUAUACUACUCAGGAGAUGGGUGCACCAGGAUCUCACAAAUCACCACUAAAGAAUUUACUCAUGUAACCAAAUACCACCUGUACCCCCAAUAACUUAUGGGAAAAAAAGAUAUUCAUCGACCUAUUCCAGGUCCUCUCUCCACCACUGAGCCUCGUGGGGACAUAAAGAGCUGCCUGCCCUCCCCUGUUCCCCUUGCCUUUUUGCAGCAGGAUUCCUGAAAAUGUUGACUUACAGAUACGUUUUUGAGAUAUGAACGUUUGUUAUUUCCUGGUGCUUAGGGAAGAAAAUAAUUGAUGUUGUGAGUUGGGCGGGACUUUAGGGACUAUGCUGAACAAUCCACUGACCACUGCAGGCUCCCAUUUAUGAUCUUGGGCCAACAGCCACCAGCCUCUGUUCAUGCAGUCUCACUGAGGGCAGUUACUUCUUUGGAGUGGCAUGCCUCUGAGCAGAUAAUUCCAAUAAUCAAUGUCAAACUAGAUAUUGAAACAGCCCAAGUGUCCUGGUAAAGCUAGCUGUUGAUACUCCUGACUGUUGCAUUAUUUUGUUUUUUGUUUUGUUUUGUUUUGAGACGGAGUCUUGCUCUGUCACCCAGGCUGGAGUGCAAUGGUGCGAUCUUGGCUCACUGCAAGCUGUGCCUCCCGGGUUCAAACAAUUCUUCUGCCUCAGCCUCCCGAGUAGCUGGGAUUACAGGUGCAUGCCACCAUGCCCAGCUAAUUUUGUAUUUUUAGUAGAGACAGGGUUUCACCAUGUUGUCCAGGCUGGUCUUGAACUCCUGACCUCAAGUGAUCCACCCACCUUGGCCUCCCAAGGUGCUGGGAUUACAGGCACAAGCCACAGCUCCCGGCCCAACUGUUGCAUUAUUAUUUGCAAAUGUUGGCUAUCCCUGCUGUUGUCUAUAUAUCAAUUUUGUCUACCCAACACAGCUGUAAACUUCUCAAGGUGAGGAGUGAGCCAUCACUCUUUGCACCUCUUGCUGUGAUUGACAUGGUAUACCUUAAGAUAUAUGUUAAUUCCUAUGUCUUAAUAAAUAUUGGCUUAUGGAGAAUUUGUUGGAGCAAGUACAGACCCUAUGUUUAACUUCUUUUAUUCAACAGAAUUAAAAAACUAGCUAGUUCUCUCAAUAAAAUAAUACUUUCUUUUCUUUCUUAAAAUCUAGCUGAUCUGGUCUAAAAUACACAUGUGGGAGGCGGGAUUGUAGAAAUAUCUCAAAUUAAUUAGCGUCUAGCUCUUUGUAAGGUAAUUGACAGUCUGAGUUAGUUGCUUCCCCCACUGCAAAGCAGCAAAAUCUGCUCUCAAAGGCUUCACGUAGCCGGGAAAACUCCGUUCCCAAUUCAGAUCCUCUGGGGAGGGCAUCAAUUAUUUCCUAUUGUUUUUAGCACCGAUUGUUCUGUCUAAUUUGAAAGGAUCCAAAAAAGGAAAUGAUACUUGGCAUUAGUAUCAUUCUCCAUCACUCUUGAAAGAUAUAUGAAGGGAAUGUUGGCGCAAUCAGUCUAGAAACAUAUUUCUCCCAUAACAAUAAGCCAGUUCUUUUUGCUUUGAAUCAGAAAUAGCUCCAUCAGGCCCAUGAAGGAAAGGGAAACAAAACUGAGUGCCAAGCAUAUGAUAACAUGCUCAGCAUCAUAUGACAUUAGGGGAUUGCAAAUUGAAACAACAGUACCACCACACACCUAUCAGAAUGGCCAAAAUCCAGAAGACUGACAUCACCAAUGCUAGUGAGAAUGUGGAGCAACAGGAACUCUCAUUCACGGCUGGUGGGGAUGCAAAGUGGUGGAGCCACUUGGGAAGACAGUCUGGCAGAUUCCUAAAAAGGUAAACAUACUCUUACUAAACAAUCUAGUAGAUUUGCUCCUAGGUGUUUACCCAAAGGAGUUGAAAACAUGUCCACACAGAAAACCUGCACAUGAAUGUUUAUAGCAGCUUUACUCAAAAUUGCCAAAAAUUGGAAGCAACCAAGAUGUCCUUCAAUAGGUGGGCGGAUAAAGAAAUUGUAUCCAAUUCUAUUUCUAUGAGGAAAAUCUAUUCAUACAAUAGAAUACUAGUGUCAGAGAUUUUUUUUUAACAAAGAGCUAUCAAGCCAUGAAAAGAUAAGGAAGAACUUUAAUGCAUAUUGGUAAGUGAAAAAAGCCAGUUUGCAAAGGCUAGAUACUAUAUGAUCCCAACUGUAUAACAUUCUGAAAAAGGCACAACUAUGGAGACAAUAAAAAGAACAGAGUUUUGGAUGAAGGGAGGGAUGAACAGGCAGAAUACAAACAAAUUUUAGGGCAGUGAAACUAUUAUUAUGAUACUUUAUGGAUAUAGAAUAUUAUGCAUUUUUCAAAACACAUAGAAUAUACAACAUGAAGAAUGAAUGCUAAUGUAAACUCUGGAUUUUUAUUAAUAAUAUUAUUUAAUUAAAAUGAUUUAUUUUACUUAUUUUCAUUAUUAUCUAAAAUGUUAUUUAAUUAUUAAAUUUAGAUGCUACUUAAUUUUUGCUUUAUUAUUAUUAUGUUAAUAUCAUCAACUGUAACUAGUGUACAACACUAAUGCAAGAUGUUAAUAGGGGAAAUCGUGUUGGAGAGAGAGAUAUGUGAGAACUCUGUACUUUCUUUUCAAUGUUUCUGUAAACAUAAAGCUGCUCUAAAAAAUUAAAUCUAUUAAAAAAAAAACUGAGUGGAAAAA